AACACCUGGCUGGCUACGGAGGGGCGUGUCUCCGCCCCGCCCCCUCCACCGGGCUGACCGGCCUGGGAUUCCUGCCUUCUAGGUCUAGGCCCGGUGAGAGACUCCACACCGCGGAGAACUGCCAUUCUUUCCUGGGCAUCCCGGGGAUCCCAGAGCCGGCCCAGGUACCAGCAGGUUCCAAACCGGCCACACUGCAGACUCCCCACGUUGCCGCACGCGGGAAUCCAUCGUCAGGCCAUCACGCCGGGGAGGCAUCUCCUCUCUGGGGUCUCGCUCUGGUCUUCUACGUGGAAAUGAACGAGAGCCACACGCCUGCGUGUGCGAGACCGUCCCGGCAACGGCGACGCCCACAGGCAUUGCCUCCUUCACGGAGAGAGGGCCUGGCACACUCAAGACUCCCACGGAGGUUCAGUUCCACACUCCCCUCCACCCUCCCAGGCUGGUUUCUCCCUGCUGCCGACGCGUGGGAGCCCAGAGAGCGGCUUCCCGUUCCCGCGGGAUCCCUGGAGAGGUCCGGAGAGCCGGCCCCCGAAACGCGCCCCCCUCCCCCCUCCCCCCUCUCCCCCUUCCUCUUCGUCUCUCCGGCCCCACCACCACCACCGCCACCACGCCCUCCCCCACCACCCCCCCCCCCACCACCACCACCACCACCACCACCCCGCCGGCCGGCCCCAGGCCUCGACGCCCUGGGUCCCUUCCGGGGUGGGGCGGGCUGUCCCAGGGGGGCUCACCGCCAUUCAUGAAGGGGUGGAGCCUGCCUGCCUGUGGGCCUUUACAAGGGCGGCUGGCUGGCUGGCUGGCUGGCUGUCCGGGCAGGCCUCCUGGCUGCACCUGCCGCAGUGCACAGUCCGGCUGAGGUGCACGGGAGCCCGCCGGCCUCUCUCUGCCCGCGUCCGUCCGUGAAAUUCCGGCCGGGGCUCACCGCGAUGGCCCUCCCGACACCCUCGGACAGCACCCUCCCCGCGGAAGCCCGGGGACGAGGACGGCGACGGAGACUCGUUUGGACCCCGAGCCAAAGCGAGGCCCUGCGAGCCUGCUUUGAGCGGAACCCGUACCCGGGCAUCGCCACCAGAGAACGGCUGGCCCAGGCCAUCGGCAUUCCGGAGCCCAGGGUCCAGAUUUGGUUUCAGAAUGAGAGGUCACGCCAGCUGAGGCAGCACCGGCGGGAAUCUCGGCCCUGGCCCGGGAGACGCGGCCCGCCAGAAGGCCGGCGAAAGCGGACCGCCGUCACCGGAUCCCAGACCGCCCUGCUCCUCCGAGCCUUUGAGAAGGAUCGCUUUCCAGGCAUCGCCGCCCGGGAGGAGCUGGCCAGAGAGACGGGCCUCCCGGAGUCCAGGAUUCAGAUCUGGUUUCAGAAUCGAAGGGCCAGGCACCCGGGACAGGGUGGCAGGGCGCCCGCGCAGGCAGGCGGCCUGUGCAGCGCGGCCCCCGGCGGGGGUCACCCUGCUCCCUCGUGGGUCGCCUUCGCCCACACCGGCGCGUGGGGAACGGGGCUUCCCGCACCCCACGUGCCCUGCGCGCCUGGGGCUCUCCCACAGGGGGCUUUCGUGAGCCAGGCAGCGAGGGCCGCCCCCGCGCUGCAGCCCAGCCAGGCCGCGCCGGCAGAGGGGAUCUCCCAACCUGCCCCGGCGCGCGGGGAUUUCGCCUACGCCGCCCCGGCUCCUCCGGACGGGGCGCUCUCCCACCCUCAGGCUCCUCGGUGGCCUCCGCACCCGGGCAAAAGCCGGGAGGACCGGGACCCGCAGCGCGACGGCCUGCCGGGCCCCUGCGCGGUGGCACAGCCUGGGCCCGCUCAAGCGGGGCCGCAGGGCCAAGGGGUGCUUGCGCCACCCACGUCCCAGGGGAGUCCGUGGUGGGGCUGGGGCCGGGGUCCCCAGGUCGCCGGGGCGGCGUGGGAACCCCAAGCCGGGGCAGCUCCACCUCCCCAGCCCGCGCCCCCGGACGCCUCCGCCUCCGCGCGGCAGGGGCAGAUGCAAGGCAUCCCGGCGCCCUCCCAGGCGCUCCAGGAGCCGGCGCCCUGGUCUGCACUCCCCUGCGGCCUGCUGCUGGAUGAGCUCCUGGCGAGCCCGGAGUUUCUGCAGCAGGCGCAACCUCUCCUAGAAACGGAGGCCCCGGGGGAGCUGGAGGCCUCGGAAGAGGCCGCCUCGCUGGAAGCACCCCUCAGCGAGGAAGAAUACCGGGCUCUGCUGGAGGAGCUUUAGGACGCGGGGUUGGGACGGGGUCGGGUGGUUCGGGGCAGGGCGGUGGCCUCUCUUUCGCGGGGAACACCUGGCUGGCUACGGAGGGGCGUGUCUCCGCCCCGCCCCCUCCACCGGGCUGACCGGCCUGGGAUUCCUGCCUUCUAGGUCUAGGCCCGGUGAGAGACUCCACACCGCGGAGAACUGCCAUUCUUUCCUGGGCAUCCCGGGGAUCCCAGAGCCGGCCCAGGUACCAGCAGGUGGGCCGCCUACUGCGCACGCGCGGGUUUGCGGGCAGCCGCCUGGGCUGUGGGAGCAGCCCGGGCAGAG